ACUACUCCAGACAGACGGCUUUGGAAUCCACCAGCUACAUCCAGCUCCCUGAGGCAGGAUGAGAUCUGCUCACCAAGCAGGAGAGGAGCAGGCAUUCUGAUUGGACUGAACCUCGGACCCCCCAUCAGCUUACAGACCGAGGAGCCAGGCAAACCUGGCUGCCCACUGGGCUCCUUUACCUGUUUGCUGUAUGAUCUUGGGCAAGCCCCCUCACCGCUCUGUGCCCGGCUUUUCCACUGCAAGAAAAUGGCAACAAUUAUGAGUUGAGAAUGGAGAGAAUGUUACCUCUCCUGGCUCUGGGGCUCUUGGCGGCUGGGUUCUGCCCUGCUGUCCUCUGCCACCCUAACAGCCCACUUGACGAGGAGAAUCUGACCCAGGAGAACCAAGACCGAGGGACACACGUGGACCUCGGAUUAGCCUCCGCCAACGUGGACUUCGCUUUCAGCCUGUACAAGCAGUUAGUCCUGAAGGCCCCUGAUAAGAAUGUCAUCUUCUCCCCACUGAGCAUCUCCACCGCCUUGGCCUUCCUGUCUCUGGGGGCCCAUAAUACCACCCUGACAGAGAUUCUCAAAGGCCUCAAGUUCAACCUCACGGAGACUUCUGAGGCAGAAAUUCACCAGAGCUUCCAGCACCUCCUGCGCACCCUCAAUCAGUCCAGCGAUGAGCUGCAGCUGAGUAUGGGAAAUGCCAUGUUUGUCAAAGAGCAACUCAGUCUGCUGGACAGGUUCACGGAGGAUGCCAAGAGGCUGUAUGGCUCCGAGGCCUUUGCCACUGACUUUCAGGACUCAGCUGCAGCUAAGAAGCUCAUCAACGACUACGUGAAGAAUGGAACUAGGGGGAAAAUCACAGAUCUGAUCAAGGACCUUGACUCGCAGACAAUGAUGGUCCUGGUGAAUUACAUCUUCUUUAAAGCCAAAUGGGAGAUGCCCUUUGACCCCCAAGAUACUCAUCAGUCAAGGUUCUACUUGAGCAAGAAAAAGUGGGUAAUGGUGCCCAUGAUGAGUUUGCAUCACCUGACUAUACCUUACUUCCGGGACGAGGAGCUGUCCUGCACCGUGGUGGAGCUGAAGUACACAGGCAAUGCCAGCGCACUCUUCAUCCUCCCUGAUCAAGACAAGAUGGAGGAAGUGGAAGCCAUGCUGCUCCCAGAGACCCUGAAGCGGUGGAGAGACUCUCUGGAGUUCAGAGAGAUAGGUGAGCUCUACCUGCCAAAGUUUUCCAUCUCGAGGGACUAUAACCUGAACGACAUACUUCUCCAGCUGGGCAUUGAGGAAGCCUUCACCAGCAAGGCUGACCUGUCAGGGAUCACAGGGGCCAGGAACCUAGCAGUCUCCCAGGUGGUCCAUAAGGCUGUGCUUGAUGUAUUUGAGGAGGGCACAGAAGCAUCUGCUGCCACAGCAGUCAAAAUCACCCUCCUUUCUGCAUUAGUGGAGACAAGGACCAUUGUGCGUUUCAACAGGCCCUUCCUGAUGAUCAUUGUCCCUACAGACACCCAGAACAUCUUCUUCAUGAGCAAAGUCACCAAUCCCAAGCAAGCCUAGAGCUUGCCAUCAAGCAGUGGGGCUCUCAGUAAGGAACUUGGAAUGCAAGCUGGAUGCCUGGGUCUCUGGGCACAGCCUGGCCCCUGUGCACCGAGUGGCCAUGGCAUGUGUGGCCCUGUCUGCUUAUCCUUGGAAGGUGACAGCGAUUCCCUGUGUAGCUCUCACAUGCACAGGGGCCCAUGGACUCUUCAGUCUGGAGGGUCCUGGGCCUCCUGACAGCAAUAAAUAAUUUCGUUGGA